ACAUGAGCCACCAAAAUGGUGGUGUUCGGGUAUGAGGCUGGGACUAAGCCAAGGGAUUCAGGUGUGGUGCCGGUGGGAACUGAGGAAGCGCCCAAGGAAAUGAAACACGAUUUCCAAAAUGAACUUAAUCUUUCAUGAGAAACUGAGGAUAGAGAUGUCAAUAAGCAGCCACUGUUUCCACCUCCCCACCUGAAGAGCUAGGAGGACAACUACAAAGAGCCUGACUGCCUUCUCGGAAUGAGGAGAGAGGAAAACAGCAACAGUAUCAGUUUUCAAGAUGGCAGCAUCUAUGCAUGGUCAGCCCAGUCCUUCUCUAGAAGAUGCAAAACUCAGAAGACCAAUGGUCAUAGAAAUCAUAGAAAAAAAUUUUGACUAUCUUAGAAAAGAAAUGACACAAAAUAUAUAUCAAAUGGCGACAUUUGGAACAACAGCUGGUUUCUCUGGAAUAUUCUCAAACUUCCUGUUCAGACGCUGCUUCAAGGUUAAACAUGAUGCUUUGAAGACAUAUGCAUCAUUGGCUACACUUCCAUUUUUGUCUACUGUUGUUACUGACAAGCUUUUUGUAAUUGAUGCUUUGUAUUCAGGUGAAUUUAAAUUCACUAAUGUAUAACGUAGUUAUGUCUAAGUAAAGUUACUUAUUAACAUAUACUGUUGCUACUGCUAAUAAUAAUUCUUUACAUUUAUAUAUUGCUAUACAGUUUACAAAGUCCAUAUACCUUGUCAUAUUUAAUCCCUGCAACAAUCCUCCUAAUCAGGUAAACUGUAUUUUUUUAUUUCUGUAGAUAAGCAACCCAAACUGAGGCAUGUUCAAGUACGCUAAUAAGCAACAUACUGGGAAAAGAAUUGGCUGUGGCAUACAACGCACAUCAUUUCAGUAUGCUACCUCCUGCCACUUAAGUUUUGUGACAUUCAGUAAGGCAUUUCAUCUCUGAGCCUCCGUUGUCUUAUCUAUAAGUUAGGACUAAUAGUACUUACCUCACAGGAUUGUUGUGAGAAUUAAAAGAUACUGUAGGUUAAAUGACUACCACAAUAUCUGUCAUAUUAUGGGCUUUUAAUGUUAUUUCCUGCCCCUCACCUUACCUUGAGUUUCACAACUAGUAAUUGAUAGAGCAUCUAUCCCUUGUUCAUUCUUCAGGUUCCUGCUUAAGUAUCUUUUCCCCAGGGAGACCUCUGAUUGCCUCAUUGUACACUAGGUGUCUGGAUACAUUCUCUAUAUAGUUUAUCUUCAAAGUAUUGUGUACACUGAUAAUUAUCUAUUUAAAUAUUUAUCUCGUGUCUUUCAUCUCUGUAAACUGGCCAGAAGGUCAGAGAUCAGGUCUCUUUUAUGUACCACCGUAUUCCUAGCUCCUAGCACGUUCCUGAUAUAUAGUAGAUAAUAAAAAUGUAUUAACCUAGAAUCCAGGUCUGGUUUGCUAGUUUAGUAUUGUCAUUAUAAAAUUGUUUCUGGCUGGGCACGGUGGCUCAUGCCUAUAAUCCCAACACUUUGGGAGGCCAAGACAGGCAGAUCACUUGAGGUCAGGAGUUCGAGACCAGCCUGGCCAACACAGUCUCUACUAAAAAUAGAAAAACAGUUGAGCAUGGUGGUGCAAGCUUAUAAUCCCAGCUACUUGGGAGGCUGAGGCAUGAGAAUUGCUUGAACCCUGGAGGCAGAGGUUGCAGUGAGCCGAGAUCGUGCCACUGUACUCUAGCCUGGGCAACAGAGUGAGACUCCGUCUCCAAAAAAUAAAAUAAAAUUGCUUCUACAACAACCACAUACGUUAGAGGUAAUUCUCUAUGUGAUAAAGUAUAAUAAAAACUUUUUAAAAUGUGC